GGUUGCGGUAGGGACGGGUGGCGUCCGGGUGUCUGGACUCAGUUCGGGCUCCGUUGUACGGCUUCGGACUUACGAUUUGUUUCUUUGAGCCUCAGUUUCCUCCCCUGUGGAAUGGGGGUUAGAAUCCGACUGUAUCACCGGCUUUAUAAAUGGGAGUGAGAAGUCAGGUCGUGUACGUUGGAUGCCUUAGCUCAGCGCCUCCGCAUAACGCUCACUUCGUUACUAUACUAUUAUUAUUAGUAUUGAUGUUUGAGCGCUUAGUAUGAAAAAUUGUUGGGUUUGGAAGCCGUCGAAUUUUGGUUCAAGUCCCGCUCCACUGUGCGGCAGUGGGGCCUGUGUCUUCGCUUCCUUGAACCCCGUUUUUUCUCAUCUGUACAAUGAGAGCAGAUAGUCCCAAUAUCAUAGGGUCGUCUUGAGGAUUCUGAUGAAAUCUGUGUGUGUAAAGAUUUUAAGCAGAGGGGCUGGCACAGUGAGAGCUCGUGGAUUGGGACUAUAAUGAUAAUGAUUCUGAGAGUCAUUGGUGUAGCUGGGAAUUCCAGGGAAGCUGGGGGAGAAAGCUCAGAGACAGCAAUAGGAAAAACUUAGAAUUGGAGCCGGGGAAAUCGACAUCCUGUCACUUACUAUUUGACCAAUUUUGCUGAGUCCUGAAGUACUAGUUUUUUUCUUUUUCUUGAUAAUGACUAGUGCAUUUUUUUCCCCAGUAAGUUAAUUUGAGAAGGCAAAUUUGCAUUGCUGUCUUCUUCUUUUUUUUUUCUUUGAGACGGAGUUUCGCUCUUGUUGCCCAGGCUGGAGUGCAAUGGUGCAAUUUCGUCUCACCGCAACCUCCGCUUCCUGGGUUCAAGGGAUUCUCCUGCCUCAACCUUCCGAGUAGCUGGGAUUACAGGCAUGCGCCACCACGCCCGGCUAAUUUUUUUUGUAUUUUAGUAGAGACGGGGUUUCUGCAUGUUGGUCAGGCUGGUCUCGAACUUCUGACUUCAGGUGAUCUGCCCGCCUCUGCCUCCCAAAGUGCUGGGAUUACAGGUGUGAGCCACCGUGCCCGGCGCAUUGCUGUCUUCAAUGGAAAACUAGCAUUGCUGGCCAUGAGAGGAAGGAAAAGUUCAGAAACUCAUCCAGCCCUUAUAGCAGUCCUCUAAGGCUCCAGGGAGCAGUGUCAGGGCCAGGGAGACGAUGGUCUCCGUGACUAUGGCCACUUCCGAGUGGAUCCAGUUCUUUAAGGAAGCCGGCAUUCCUCCAGGACCUGCCGUCAAUUAUGCCGUGAUGUUUGUGGAUAAUAGGAUUCAGAAGAGCAUGCUGCUGGAUCUCAAUAAGGAGAUAAUGAAUGAGCUGGGCGUGACCGUGGUGGGUGACAUCAUCGCCAUUCUCAAGCAUGCCAAAGUGGUGCACCGUCAGGACAUGUGCAAAGCUGCCACUGAGUCAGUACCCUGCAGCCCUAGCCCCCUUGCAGGCGAAAUUCGCCGUGGCACCAGUGCUGCCUCCCGAAUGAUCACCAACAGCCUGAACCAUGACUCUCCACCCAGCACACCCCCCAGGCGCCCGGACACCAGCACCUCCAAGAUCUCGGUCACUGUGUCCAACAAGAUGGCAGCAAAGAGUGCCAAGGCCACUGCAGCCCUGGCCCGCCGGGAGGAGGAGAGCCUGGCUGUUCCUGCCAAGCGGCGCCGGGUCACUGCUGAGAUGGAGGGGAAGUACGUCAUCAACAUGCCCAAAGGCACCACACCCCGCACCCGCAAGAUCCUGGAGCAGCAGCAGGCUGCAAAAGGUCUCCAUAGGACGUCUGUGUUUGACCGCCUCGGCGCCGAGACCAAGGCAGACACCACGACAGGGAGUAAACCCACAGGAGUCUUCAGCCGCCUGGGGGCCACCCCAGAAACGGACGAGGAUCUGGCUUGGGACAGCGACAAUGACAGCAGCAGCUCUGUCUUGCAGUAUGCCGGGGUCCUGAAGAAGCUAGGACGGGGCCCAGCCAAGGCCAGUCCCCAGCCAGCACUGACUGUCAAAGCCAAGGCCACAAGCUCAGCGACAACGGCUGCUGCCCCGACACUGCGGCGCCUGGCGCUUUCCUCACGGUCUGGGCUUGAGAGGAAGCCGGAGUCCUUGUCUAAAGUCAGCAUCAUCAAGAGACUGGGCGCAGCUGCCCUUGUGCCCGAGGCCCAGGACAGCCAGGUCACCAGCACCAAGAGUAAGUCCUCAGCCGAGGUCAAGGUCACCAUUAAGAGGACUCUGGUGGGGCCCCGGGGGAGCAGCUCCAGCGAGGGCCUUGGUGCCCAGAUGGACCACGCGGGCACUGUGAGCGUGUUCAAAAGACUGGGCCGCAGGACCUUCUAGCCCACCUGUGGGCGGGGUGCAGGCAGCAGAGCCUGCGGGCAUCUGCCCUGGCCGCCCCAGGCUCCUGGCUUCAUCACGCCUCCCACCAGCUCCUGGAUGACACAGCUUGUCUCCCUCGGGCUCUAGAGCUAGGCCCGAGCAUUCGGGGGAUCACCCCAUUUCUCCUAGCCUGGGAUGGUCGUCGCAGCUGGCCUGGCCUGCUCCAGGACUCCCCUUCUCUCAUGUCCUCUGUGCUUUCUUCUCUGGCUGUGGCCUUGGCAGAACCCACUUUUCUACCUCUCCCAAGUGCCAGGGGGCUUCUUCCUCUCCUACAUUCCCCUUCUUCCCCUGAGCAGGGUCUGCUGCCUCAGACCCCAGCUCAUCAGCCUCCCUGUCCCCCUCAACUAAGUGGGUGUCACCUGGUGGGCCUCCCUUCCCCCACUCCCCACUGACCUCCCUCACUCCUCUGCGCCUCCCCCCACUGCUGUGACUUCUCUCUCUCCCUGUCUUCACUUUGUUCAUUUCUCUUCUGUUUUCUGUCCCCGUGGCAAGGCCCGACUGUCCGCUGCGUCCUGCCCGACCCUCCUGUACCUCCGGCCUCCCAGCGGCCCCCUCGUCGGCGGUGGCGUCGAGCCUGUUGAGACUGUUAGCCGCCCUCUACUCCCAGGCUGGAGGGACCUCUCCAGACCCUGGGCUGCGGCUGAGGCGCAUCCGUUUUCCUGCCCUGGGCAUCUGUCUCUGAAAGUGUAUGGCGGGUGGUGGGCAAGGGGCACUGGGAAGGGAGGCCAGUGCCUAGAGUGAAGACAGCUGCUGUUUUAAUAUAUUUUUGUGACUUUCAAAUCAUUUCCCCCACUCCUUCAGGGUGAGUUGCAGGACUGUUUCACACUAUGCGCAGCUGGGCUGGGGAUGGUGGCAGAGGAUUGGGCUGUGUCUCUAAAGGUCAGGCUUCCUGCACACACAUGGUCCAUGUCCCUGCUGCAAGCCCUGAGUCAGGGGGAGUAAUGGCCACAGUCACCAUUCAGUUAGGCCGCCCCCUGCCCCCAAUAAGCCGUAGUGGUUUUGUCACUCUAUCCCCUCCCCCCAUGGAUUUCACCUGCCUGCUGGCACCUUUCCAAAUGAUGGGCUCCGUUUGUGAGACCAUGAGUUUCCACUGGUUUGGUCGCCCACCCCUCCCUGCUGCACAGCGCCCCUGAGCCAGGCCUGUCCUAGGAGCUGGUAGCAGGUAGUGAGCAGGGCCUCUCCAGGGAUGGGGUGUAGGUAAAGCGGUGGUGCUGGCCAAGGAAUCUGAGGAGUGGGAGAAAGUGGCCAGGGCCGCUUCAGUGGUUGUGGAUAGGAAGGCCUUGCAGAAGGGGUGACAUGGAGGCCAAGUUGGGAAUGUGGCUUCAUGAAGUUCAGGAGGAGAGCUUUCAGACAGAGGGACAGCCAGGGGCAGAGGUGCUGAGGUGGGACAAGGAACAGGAAGAAGGCUGGUGGCUGUGGGUGAGGGUGGGCCCUGCCUCCAGCAUGAGGCAGAGGUGGGUGGGCAGGGGCUAGGUGGCUGGGGGUGUUGUGAUCAAGGAGGAGGAAUGUGCACAGUGACCCGGGAGUGCUGGAUCGGGAGGAUUUGGAGCUGGGAUGUGCUGAGCUGAGUUUCAUUUAGGAUCAUCGCUCUGGCUUCUGUGAGGAGAAGGAAUGGCUGGGAGGGCUGGGGUGGAUGCCACUGCAGCAGUCCAGGCAGGAAGCCAGGAUGGCUGCGAGGGCAUGGCAGUGGGGAGCAGGGAAGAGGGCCGCUUGGGCUGCUUAGGGUGUGCUUUGGAGGAAGAGCUGUGGGAUGUGCUGAUGGGUUGGAAGUUGGGGCUAGAGAAGAUGAGAAUCAUAGGGCCCGCCUAGAUGUUAGACCGGAGCAUCUGGGGGAACGGCUGUUAACAGAGAAGGGGAGACGGGAGGAAGGUCAAGGAAGAGGGAGCUGUGUUCUGACUGCAUUGCGCCUGUUAGGGUCCCCGCUGGGGCUCAGGCGGACACCUGGGCUGGGGGUUCAUGGCUGCUGACAGUGCGCAGGGUACAGCUGGAAUCAAAGCCAAGGGCCUUGGCUGGGCGUGGUGGCUUACGCUUGUAAUCCCAGCAGUUUGGGAGGCCAAGGCGGGUGGAUCACAAGGUCAGGAGUUCGAGACCAGCCUGGCCAAGAUGGUGAAACCCCGUCUCUACUAAAAAUACAAAAAUUAGCCGGGUGUGGUGACAGGUGCCUGUAAUCCCGGCUACUUAGGAGGCUGAGGCAGGAGGAUCGCUUGAACCCGGGAGGUGGAGGUUGCAGUGAGCUGAGAUCGUGCCACUGCACUCCAGCCUAGGCAACAAGAGCGAGACUCCAUCUCAAAAAAAAAAAAAAAAAAA